GGCUUCCGGCCGCCUUCCGCGGCCACCGCCGGGCCCGCUCCCGCCGCCGACGCCCAGGUGCGCCAGGUGCGGGCCGGGCGGGGGUCGCGCUCACCUUUCUGGCCGCUGAGUGCCGCGUACCAGGACAGCGAGAGGAAGGCGCACAGGCAGAAGAGCAGCAGCGUCAGGAAGGUGCCAUUGCGGAGCCUCAUCUCCUCGGUGUCUGCGAGAUUAAUCUCUCAUGGCCGCUGCACAAGAACCUGGCUUUUAGCUGAACUAAGGAGAAAGUCCUACAACAGUUUGGCGUGCAACAUGGGGCUUGAGAAAGGAUGAGGACGGGGACUUGGUUGCCUUUUCCAGUGACGAGGAAUUGACAAUGGCCAUGUCCUACGUGAAGGAUGACAUCUUCCGAAUCUACAUUAAAGAGAAAAAAGAGUGCCGGCGGGACCACCGCCCACCGUGUGCUCAGGAGGCGCCCCGCAACAUGGUGCACCCCAAUGUGAUCUGCGAUGGCUGCAAUGGGCCUGUGGUAGGAACCCGCUACAAGUGCAGCGUCUGCCCAGACUACGACUUGUGUAGCGUCUGCGAGGGAAAGGGCUUGCACCGGGGGCACACCAAGCUCGCAUUCCCCAGCCCCUUCGGGCACCUGUCUGAGGGCUUCUCGCACAGCCGCUGGCUCCGGAAGGUGAAACACGGACACUUCGGGUGGCCAGGAUGGGAAAUGGGUCCACCAGGAAACUGGAGCCCACGUCCUCCUCGUGCAGGGGAGGCCCGCCCUGGCCCCACGGCAGAAUCAGCUUCUGGUCCAUCGGAGGAUCCGAGUGUGAAUUUCCUGAAGAACGUUGGGGAGAGUGUGGCAGCUGCCCUUAGCCCUCUGGGCAUUGAAGUUGAUAUCGAUGUGGAGCACGGAGGGAAAAGAAGCCGCCUGACCCCCGUCUCUCCAGAGAGUUCCAGCACAGAGGAGAAGAGCAGCUCACAGCCAAGCAGCUGCUGCUCUGACCCCAGCAAGCCGGGUGGGAAUGUUGAGGGCGCCACGCAGUCUCUGGCGGAGCAGAUGAGGAAGAUCGCCUUGGAGUCCGAGGGGCGCCCUGAGGAACAGAUGGAGUCGGAUAACUGUUCAGGAGGAGAUGAUGACUGGACCCAUCUGUCUUCAAAAGAAGUGGACCCGUCUACAGGUGAACUCCAGUCCCUACAGAUGCCAGAAUCCGAAGGGCCAAGCUCUCUGGACCCCUCCCAGGAGGGACCCACAGGGCUGAAGGAAGCUGCCUUGUACCCACAUCUCCCGCCAGAGGCUGACCCGCGGCUGAUUGAGUCCCUCUCCCAGAUGCUGUCCAUGGGCUUCUCUGAUGAAGGCGGCUGGCUCACCAGGCUCCUGCAGACCAAGAACUAUGACAUCGGAGCGGCUCUGGACACCAUCCAGUAUUCAAAGCAUCCCCCGCCGUUGUGACCACUUUUGCCCACCUCUUCUGCGUGCCCCUCUUCUGUCUCAUAGUUGUGUUAAGCUUGCGUAGAAUUGCAGGUCUCUGUACGGGCCAGUUUCUCUGCCUUCUUCCAGGAUCAGGGGUUAGGGUGCAAGAAGCCAUUUAGGGCAGCAAAACAAGUGACAUGAAGGGAGGGUCCCUGUGUGUGUGUGUGCUGAUGUUUCCUGGGUGCCCUGGCUCCUUGCAGCAGGGCUGGGCCUGCGAGACCCAAGGCUCACUGCAGCGCGCUCCUGACCCCUCCCUGCAGGGGCUACGUUAGCAGCCCAGCACAUAGCUUGCCUAAUGGCUUUCACUUUCUCUUUUGUUUUAAAUGACUCAUAGGUCCCUGACAUUUAGUUGAUUAUUUUCUGCUACAGACCUGGUACACUCUGAUUUUAGAUAAAGUAAGCCUAGGUGUUGUCAGCAGGCAGGCUGGGGAGGCCAGUGUUGUGGGCUUCCUGCUGGGACUGAGAAGGCUCACGAAGGGCAUCCGCAAUGUUGGUUUCACUGAGAGCUGCCUCCUGGUCUCUUCACCACUGUAGUUCUCUCAUUUCCAAACCAUCAGCUGCUUUUAAAAUAAGAUCUCUUUGUAGCCAUCCUGUUAAAUUUGUAAACAAUCUAAUUAAAUGGCAUCAGCACUUUAACCAAUGACGUUUGCAUAGAGAGAAAUGAUUGACAGUAAGUUUAUUGUUAAUGGUUCUUACAGAGUAUCUUUAAAAGUGCCUUAGGGGAACCCUGUCCCUCCUAACAAGUGUAUCUCGAUUAAUAACCUGCCAGUCCCAGAUCACACAUCAUCAUCGAAGUCUUCCCCAGUUAUAAAGAGGUCACAUAGUCGUGUGGGUCGAGGAUUCUGUGCCUCCAGGACCAGGGGCCCACCCUCUGCCCAGGGAGUCCUUGCGUCCCAUGAGGUCUUCCCGCAAGGCCUCUCAGACCCAGAUGUGACGGGGUGUGUGGCCCGAGGAAGCUGGACAGCGGCAGUGGGCCUGCUGAGGCCUUCUCUUGAGGCCUGUGCUCUGGGGGUCCCUUGCUUAGCCUGUGCUGGACCAGCUGGCCUGGGGUCCCUCUGAAGAGACCUUGGCUGCUCACUGUCCACAUGUGAACUUUUUCUAGGUGGCAGGACAAAUUGCGCCCAUUUAGAGGAUGUGGCUGUAACCUGCUGGAUGGGACUCCAUAGCUCCUUCCCAGGACCCCUCAGCUCCCCGGCACUGCAGUCUGCAGAGUUCUCCUGGAGGCAGGGGCUGCUGCCUUGUUUCACCUUCCAUGUCAGGCCAGCCUGUCCCUGAAAGAGAAGAUGGCCAUGCCCUCCAUGUGUAAGAACAAUGCCAGGGCCCAGGAGGACCGCCUGCCCUGCCUGGGCCUUGGCUGGGCCUCUGGUUCUGACACUUUCUGCUGGAAGCUGUCAGGCUGGGACAGGCUUUGAUUUUGAGGGUUAGCAAGACAAAGCAAAUAAAUGCCUUCCACCUCACCGCAAA